GCUCACUCCAUGUGAGGCCCCAGUCGGGGCAGCCACCUGCCGUGCCUGUUGGAAGUUGCCUCUGCCAUGCUGGGCCCUGCUGUCCUGGGCCUCAGCCUCUGGGCUCUCCUGCACCCUGGGACGGGGGCCCCAUUGUGCCUGUCACAGCAACUUAGGAUGAAGGGGGACUACGUGCUGGGGGGGCUGUUCCCCCUGGGCGAGGCCGAGGAGGCUGGCCUCCGCAGCCGGACACGGCCCAGCAGCCCUGUGUGCACCAGGUUCUCCUCAAACGGCCUGCUCUGGGCACUGGCCAUGAAAAUGGCCGUGGAGGAGAUCAACAACAAGUCGGAUCUGCUGCCCGGGCUGCGCCUGGGCUACGACCUCUUUGAUACGUGCUCGGAGCCUGUGGUGGCCAUGAAGCCCAGCCUCAUGUUCCUGGCCAAGGCAGGCAGCCGCGACAUCGCCGCCUACUGCAACUACACGCAGUACCAGCCCCGUGUGCUGGCUGUCAUCGGGCCCCACUCGUCAGAGCUCGCCAUGGUCACCGGCAAGUUCUUCAGCUUCUUCCUCAUGCCCCAGGUCAGCUACGGUGCUAGCAUGGAGCUGCUGAGCGCCCGGGAGACCUUCCCCUCCUUCUUCCGCACCGUGCCCAGCGACCGUGUGCAGCUGACGGCCGCCGCGGAGCUGCUGCAGGAGUUCGGCUGGAACUGGGUGGCCGCCCUGGGCAGCGACGACGAGUACGGCCGGCAGGGCCUGAGCAUCUUCUCGGCCCUGGCCGCGGCACGCGGCAUCUGCAUCGCGCACGAGGGCCUGGUGCCGCUGCCCCGUGCCGAUGACUCGCGGCUGGGGAAGGUGCAGGACGUCCUGCACCAGGUGAACCAGAGCAGCGUGCAGGUGGUGCUGCUGUUCGCCUCCGUGCACGCCGCCCACGCCCUCUUCAACUACAGCAUCAGCAGCAGGCUCUCGCCCAAGGUGUGGGUGGCCAGCGAGGCCUGGCUGACCUCUGACCUGGUCAUGGGGCUGCCCGGCAUGGCCCAGAUGGGCACGGUGCUUGGCUUCCUCCAGAGGGGUGCCCAGCUGCACGAGUUCCCCCAGUACGUGAAGACGCACCUGGCCCUGGCCACCGACCCGGCCUUCUGCUCUGCCCUGGGCGAGAGGGAGCAGGGUCUGGAGGAGGACGUGGUGGGCCAGCGCUGCCCGCAGUGUGACUGCAUCACGCUGCAGAACGUGAGCGCAGGGCUAAAUCACCACCAGACGUUCUCUGUCUACGCAGCUGUGUAUAGCGUGGCCCAGGCCCUGCACAACACUCUUCAGUGCAACGCCUCAGGCUGCCCCGCGCAGGACCCCGUGAAGCCCUGGCAGCUCCUGGAGAACAUGUACAACCUGACCUUCCACGUGGGCGGGCUGCCGCUGCGGUUCGACAGCAGCGGAAACGUGGACAUGGAGUACGACCUGAAGCUGUGGGUGUGGCAGGGCUCAGUGCCCAGGCUCCACGACGUGGGCAGGUUCAACGGCAGCCUCAGGACAGAGCGCCUGAAGAUCCGCUGGCACACGUCUGACAACCAGAAGCCCGUGUCCCGGUGCUCGCGGCAGUGCCAGGAGGGCCAGGUGCGCCGGGUCAAGGGGUUCCACUCCUGCUGCUACGACUGUGUGGACUGCGAGGCGGGCAGCUACCGGCAAAACCCAGGUGAGCCGCCUUCCCGGCAGGCGGGGGUGGGAACGCAGCAGGGGAGGGUCCUGCCAAGUCCUGACUCUGAGACCAGAGCCCACAGGGUACAAGACGAACACCCAGCGCCCUUCUCCUCUCUCACAGACGACAUCGCCUGCACCUUUUGUGGCCAGGAUGAGUGGUCCCCGGAGCGAAGCACACGCUGCUUCCGCCGCAGGUCUCGGUUCCUGGCAUGGGGCGAGCCGGCUGUGCUGCUGCUGCUCCUGCUGCUGAGCCUGGCGCUGGGCCUUGUGCUGGCUGCUUUGGGGCUGUUCGUUCACCAUCGGGACAGCCCACUGGUUCAGGCCUCGGGGGGGCCCCUGGCCUGCUUUGGCCUGGUGUGCCUGGGCCUGGUCUGCCUCAGCGUCCUCCUGUUCCCUGGCCAGCCCAGCCCUGCCCGAUGCCUGGCCCAGCAGCCCUUGUCCCACCUCCCGCUCACGGGCUGCCUGAGCACACUCUUCCUGCAGGCGGCCGAGAUCUUCGUGGAGUCAGAACUGCCUCUGAGCUGGGCAGACCGGCUGAGUGGCUGCCUGCGGGGGCCCUGGGCCUGGCUGGUGGUGCUGCUGGCCAUGCUGGUGGAGGUCGCACUGUGCACCUGGUACCUGGUGGCCUUCCCGCCGGAGGUGGUGACGGACUGGCACAUGCUGCCCACGGAGGCGCUGGUGCACUGCCGCACACGCUCCUGGGUCAGCUUCGGCCUAGCGCACGCCACCAAUGCCACGCUGGCCUUUCUCUGCUUCCUGGGCACUUUCCUGGUGCGGAGCCAGCCGGGCUGCUACAACCGUGCCCGUGGCCUCACCUUUGCCAUGCUGGCCUACUUCAUCACCUGGGUCUCCUUUGUGCCCCUCCUGGCCAAUGUGCAGGUGGUCCUCAGGCCCGCCGUGCAGAUGGGCGCCCUCCUGCUCUGUGUCCUGGGCAUCCUGGCUGCCUUCCACCUGCCCAGGUGUUACCUGCUCAUGCGGCAGCCAGGGCUCAACACCCCCGAGUUCUUCCUGGGAGGGGGCCCUGGGGAUGCCCAAGGCCAGAAUGACGGGAACACAGGAAAUCAGGGGAAACAUGAGUGACCCAACCCUGUGAUCUCAGCCCCGGUGAACCCAGACUUAGCUGCGAUCCCCCCCAAGCCAGCAAUGACCCGUGUCUCGCUACAGAGACCCUCCCGCUCUAGGUUCUGACCCCAGGUUGUCUCCUGACCCUGACCCCACAGUGAGCCCUAGGCCUGGAGCACGUGGACACCCCUGUGACCAUCUGGGCCCCAGAGCCAAGCUGUGUCCCUGUCCCUCUGUGCCCAGACCAGGCCUGCCCAGGUAACCCAGACCCACUGUUCUGGAAAGAGGCCCGGAGGGCUCCCAGGGUACCCGCAACCCACACCGUGAGCUCAGGAAAAGGACGCAGGGAGGCCCCGGCCAGAUGGCUGGAAGCCCAAAUCAGGCCCUGCCGACCUGACCAUGUCCCACCAGGGCCCCCAUCCUGCACCCUGCCAGGCACCACAGCAGUGGGAGGCCAGGUGGGGGCACACAGGCAUAUGCCCAGGGCAGAGCCCGCCGAGGUAGGGGUGGCACCCAGCUUCCUACUCUGCCCUUUGCCCAGUGGGUAGACAGCAUCAUGACUGUCACCAGUACCAGGGACAGAGCCCAGGUGGGGUGGGGGCGGGGUCCAGCACCACGGCCAGCACCGACCACCAGGACCCCGGAGCCAGCACCAUGGACAGAAAACUGCCCACCAGGAUCUGACGCCAGCACGCCGCCAGGCCCACACAGGGUCUCCGGUCAGAGUCCCAGGGUCAGCUCCCAGCAGGGCCUAGGGGAGGCUGGACCAGCUCCCUGUGCCUCAUUCCAAGGCAGCCCAGCCGGAGAGAAGGGGCACAGGCCACACAUCUGUCCCAUAAAAUUAAACGCUUUUUAGUGUUUAAAAUAA